GUAUUGGGGUACAGGGCUGCCCUGAGACCUCAUAACCUCUACAUCUAGGAAGAACUGCCCUCCACUUCCAAAUGUAAGAAAGGACAUUUUCUUUGUAGCUUGAGGGAUAGAGGUGUCACUGUAGAAGGGAUUUCUCCUCUUUUGGGUGAAGGGUUAGAAAUUCCAUCAAGUGAGAAGAGCACACCUCCCCUGGCCCUUCCCCACAAGUGCCUAUACUCUAGGUGAGGGAGCCAGGUGGGAUGAUGCUUUGGGGGGAGAUGCCUAUCUGCUCAGGCCCCUGUCUUCCUCUCUCUUCCCUCUAGACCCAUCCUUUAUGUAGCUAGAAGUCAGCAGGGCUGGCAUAUCUGGUGUGCCUCAUGCUAUUUUUAAUCCCAUUCGUUCUUUUGUUUCUCCCCCACUGCUGGGGCUGGGCAGCUGGUGGCCUCCUGGGUCCCCUGCCACACCAUUCAGCUAUCUGCCUCUGAGUGUGCUUUCCAUGGGAAGCUGGGGUGGCACGAGACGGUGGCCAGGUAGCCACUUUGCAGUCUGUGCUUCUGCAAAGAACCUCAUUUCUCCUUAUUUCUGAACUUUCACCCACACACACCCUCUUAUGAAGCCUCAGUUUCUCCUCUUCCAUCACGCAUUUACUGUGGGCAUCUUAAUGCCCUGGCUCAGGUGUGGGCACUGAAAAUACAGAGCUCUAAGUCCCAGCCUUAGACCCUUCAGUCCCCACCCCCACCCCUGGUUCUGGGUGCACACAGAUCCACAGAAGAAAGGCCUAGGAAAGGCGUUUGCUAUUAUUGUCCUAUGCCUGUCUCCUGGGAUCUCUAACCCCUGGGGGCGCUCGUUUUGUUUUUUGCUUCCCCCUGUUAAGAGGAGGAUGGGAGCUAGCUGGUAACAGGACCCAGGCGUCCUGGCUGAGGACCGACUCCUCUGUCCCUGCUCCAGAUUGACGAGAUGCCUGAGGCUGCCGUGAAAUCAACAGCCAACAAAUACCAAGUCUUUUUUUUCGGGACCCACGAGACGGCAUUCCUGGGCCCCAAAGACCUCUUCCCUUACGAGGAAUCCAAGGAGAAGUUUGGCAAGCCCAACAAGAGGAAAGGGUUCAGCGAGGGGCUGUGGGAGAUCGAGAACAACCCUACUGUCAAGGCUUCCGGCUAUCAGUCCUCCCAGAAAAAGAGCUGUGUGGAAGAGCCUGAACCAGAGCCCGAAGCUGCAGAGGGUGACGGUGAUAAGAAGGGGAAUGCAGAGGGCAGCAGCGACGAGGAAGGGAAGCUGGUCAUUGAUGAGCCAGCCAAGGAGAAGAACGAGAAAGGAGCGUUGAAGAGGAGAGCAGGGGACUUGCUGGAGGACUCUCCUAAACGUCCCAAGGAGGCAGAAAACCCUGAAGGAGAGGAGAAGGAGGCAGCCACCUUGGAGGUUGAGAGGCCCCUUCCUAUGGAGGUGGAAAAGAAUAGCACCCCCUCUGAGCCCGGCUCUGGCCGGGGGCCUCCCCAAGAGGAAGAAGAGGAGGAGGAUGAAGAGGAAGAGGCUACCAAGGAAGAUGCUGAGGCCCCAGGCAUCAGAGAUCAUGAGAGCCUGUAGCCACCAAUGUUUCAAGAGGAGCCCCCACCCUGUUCCUGCUGCUGUCUGGGUGCUACUGGGGAAACUGGCCAUGGCCUGCAAACUGGGAACCCCUUUCCCACCCCAACCUGCUCUCCUCUUCUACUCACUUUUCCCACUCCAAGCCCAGCCCAUGGAGAUUGACCUGGAUGGGGCAGGCCACCUGGCUCUCACCUCUAGGUCCCCAUACUCCUAUGAUCUGAGUCAGAGCCAUGUCUUCUCCCUGGAAUGAGUUGAGGCCACUGUGUUCCUUCCGCUUGGAGCUAUUUUCCAGGCUUCUGCUGGGGCCUGGGACAACUGCUCCCACCUCCUGACACCCUUCUCCCACUCUCCUAGGCAUUCUGGACCUCUGGGUUGGGAUCAGGGGUAGGAAUGGAAAGGAUGGAGCAUCAACAGCAGGGUGGGCUUGUGGGGCCUGGGAGGGGCAAUCCUCAAAUGCGGGGUGGGGGCAGCACAGGAGGGCGGCCUCCUUCUGAGCUCCUGUCCCCUGCUACACCUAUUAUCCCAGCUGCCUAGAUUCAGGGAAAGUGGGACAGCUUGUAGGGGAGGGGCUCCUUUCCAUAAAUCCUUGAUGAUUGACAACACCCAUUUUUCCUUUUGCCGACCCCAAGAGUUUUGGGAGUUGUAGUUAAUCAUCAAGAGAAUUUGGGGCUUCCAAGUUGUUCGGGCCAAGGACCUGAGACCUGAAGGGUUGACUUUACCCAUUUGGGUGGGAGUGUUGAGCAUCUGUCCCCCUUUAGAUCUCUGAAGCCACAAAUAGGAUGCUUGGGAAGACUCCUAGCUGUCCUUUUUCCUCUCCACACAGUGCUCAAGGCCAGCUUAUAGUCAUAUAUAUCACCCAGACAUAAAGGAAAAGACACAUUUUUUAGGAAAUGUUUUUAAUAAAAGAAAAUUACAAAAAAAAAUUUUAAAGACCCCUAACCCUUUGUGUGCUCUCCAUUCUGCUCCUUCCCCAUCGUUGCCCCCAUUUCUGAGGUGCACUGGGAGGCUCCCCUUCUAUUUGGGGCUUGAUGACUUUCUUUUUGUAGCUGGGGCUUUGAUGUUCCUUCCAGUGUCAUUUCUCAUCCACAUACCCUGACCUGGCCCCCUCAGUGUUGUCACCAGAUCUGAUUUGUAACCCACUGAGAGGACAGAGAGAAAUAAGUGCCCUCUCCCACCCUCUUCCUACUGGUCUCUCUAUGCCUCUCUACAGUCUCGUCUCUUUUACCCUGGCCCCUCUCCCUUGGGCUCUGAUGAAAAAUUGCUGACUGUAGCUUUGGAAGUUUAGCUCUGAGAACCGUAGAUGAUUUCAGUUCUAGGAAAAUAAAACCCGUUGAUUACUAUA